CUCCUGCCCGCCUCCGCCUUCGGAGGCUGACGCGCCCGGGCGCCGUUCCAGGCCUGUGCAGGGCGGAUCGGCAGCCGCCUGGCGGCGAUCCAGGGCGGUGCGGGGCCUGGGCGGGAGCCGGGAGGCGCGGCCGGCAUGGAGGCGCUGCUGCUGGGCGCGGGGUUGCUGCUGGGCGCUUACGUGCUUGUCUACUACAACCUGGUGAAGGCCCCGCCGUGCGGCGGCAUGGGCAACCUGCGGGGCCGCACGGCCGUGGUCACGGGCGCCAACAGCGGCAUCGGAAAGAUGACGGCGCUGGAGCUGGCGCGCCGGGGAGCGCGCGUGGUGCUGGCCUGCCGCAGCCAGGAGCGCGGGGAGGCGGCUGCCUUCGACCUCCGCCAGGAGAGUGGGAACAAUGAGGUCAUCUUCAUGGCCUUGGACUUGGCCAGUCUGGCCUCGGUGCGGGCCUUUGCCACUGCCUUUCUGAGCUCUGAGCCACGGUUGGACAUCCUCAUCCACAAUGCCGGUAUCAGUUCCUGUGGCCGGACCCGUGAGGCGUUUAACCUGCUGCUUCGGGUGAACCAUAUCGGUCCCUUUCUGCUGACACAUCUGCUGCUGCCUUGCCUGAAGGCAUGUGCCCCUAGCCGCGUGGUGGUGGUAGCCUCAGCUGCCCACUGUCGGGGACGUCUUGACUUCAAACGCCUGGACCGCCCAGUGGUGGGCUGGCGGCAGGAGCUGCGGGCAUAUGCUGACACUAAGCUGGCUAAUGUACUGUUUGCCCGGGAGCUCGCCAACCAGCUUGAGGCCACUGGCGUCACCUGCUAUGCAGCCCACCCAGGGCCUGUGAACUCGGAGCUGUUCCUGCGCCAUGUUCCUGGAUGGCUGCGCCCACUUUUGCGCCCAUUGGCUUGGCUGGUGCUCCGGGCACCAAGAGGGGGUGCCCAGACACCCCUGUAUUGUGCUCUACAAGAGGGCAUCGAGCCCCUCAGUGGGAGAUAUUUUGCCAACUGCCAUGUGGAAGAGGUGCCUCCAGCUGCCCGAGACGACCGGGCAGCCCAUCGGCUAUGGGAGGCCAGCAAGAGGCUGGCAGGGCUUGGGCCUGGGGAGGAUGCUGAACCCGAUGAAGACCCCCAGUCUGAGGACUCAGAGGCCCCAUCUUCUCUAAGCACCCCCCACCCUGAGGAGCCCACAGUUUCUCAACCUUACCCCAGCCCUCAGAGCUCACCAGAUUUGUCUAAGAUGACGCACCGAAUUCAGGCUAAAGUUGAGCCUGAGAUCCAGCUCUCCUAACCCUCAGGCCAGGAUGCUUGCCAUGGCACUUCAUGGUCCUUGAAAACCUCGGAUGUGUGCGAGGCCAUGCCCUGGACACUGACGGGUUUGUGAUCUUGACCUCCGUGGUUACUUUCUGGGGCCCCAAGCUGUGCCCUGGACAUCUCUUUUCCUGGUUGAAGGAAUAAUGGGUGAUUAUUUCUUCCUGAGAGUGACAGUAACCCCAGAUGGAGAGAUAGGGGUAUGCUAGACACUGUGCUUCUCGGAAAUUUGGAUGUAGUAUUUUCAGGCCCCACCCUUAUUGAUUCUGAUCAGCUCUGGAGCAGAGGCAGGGAGUUUGCAAUGUGAUGCACUGCCAACAUUGAGAAUUAGUGAACUGAUCCCUUUGCAACCGUCUAGCUAGGUAGUUAAAUUACCCCCAUGUUAAUGAAGCGGAAUUAGGCUCCCGAGCUAAGGGACUCGCCUAGGGUCUCACAGUGAGUAGGAGGAGGGCCUGGGAUCUGAACCCAAGGGUCUGAGGCCAGGGCCGACUGCCGUAAGAUGGGUGCUGAGAAGUGAGUCAGGGCAGGGCAGCUGGUAUCGAGGUGCCCCAUGGGAGUAAGGGGACGCCUUCCGGGCGGAUGCAGGGCUGGGGUCAUCUGUAUCUGAAGCCCCUCGGAAUAAAGCGCGUUGACCGCCGAA